AAAAUACAUAGAAUUACAAAGUAAAUCAAUUGUAUUGAAAUAUGACUGGGAUUAUAGGCACCUGGCACCACGCCCAGCUAAUUUUUUUUGUAUUUUUAGUAGAGACGGGGUUUCACCAUGUUGGCCAGGCUGGUCUCAAACUCUUAACCUUGUGAUCCACCCGCCUUGGCCUCCCAAAGUGCUGGGAUUACAGACAUGAGCCACCGCGCCCGGCCAGAAAUCAAUUGUAUUGAAAUAUGGUUAUCAGAAUAUUUAAAAAGCAAAUGUUUGAUAUAGUGAUAUAUAUCAAUGUAUUACAAUAUAUUACAAGACCUAGUGGUGAGGUUAGUAACUAAUGUAGAAGCAAUGUUAAACACAAACUAUUUUAGCAUAUCUGCAACAAUAUUCUAUGAAACUAUCUGUGCUUUCUAUUGGUGACUAUCACAGGUGCUGUGAAUACUACUGUAGUUUGUUACCAUAUUCAUAAUUGAAGAGAAUGCUAAGCUUCAAUUAGAGGUUAUUAGAAAUAAACAUAUAAUUUCUUCCCAAUCCAUGUUUAUGGACCCAGCAGGAGAGUUAGUGAAAGCUUCAGGUAAGAACACCUGCGUAGAGAAAGCAUAUGUUGGAGGCCUCUUGACUUUGUUUACAUUUGGGGAGAACAAUAGGGAGAAUUAAAUAUUUUAAUCAAAAACUUUGAAAAACGUUGGAAAACCAAAAUAGUAUUCAUUUAAAAUGGAGCAUGAUAUUAUGGUUGGAAUGUGAACUACAAAGGAACAUUAAUGUUCAUUACUUUCUAUAUAUUAUUUUGUUGAAAAGCAAAGGAUUUUUAGAAUCUUUUUAUAUAUUAUAGGUGUGAAAGUUAUUUGAAAUAUUGGCCAGGUGCUGUGGCUCACGCCUGUAAUCCCAGCACUUUGGGAGGCCGAGGGGGGUGCAUCACUUGACAAGAGUUCAAGACCAGCCUGACCGACAUGGUGAAACCCCAUCUCUACUAAAAAUACAAAAAUUAGCCGGGCAUGGUGGCAGGUACCUGUAAUCCCAACUACUUGGGAGGCUUGAGACAGGGGAAUCACUUGAACCUGGGAGGCAGAGGUUGCAGUGAGCCAAGAUCGCACCAUUGCCCUCCAGCCUGGGCGACAGAGAGAGACUCUGUCUCAAAAAAAGAAAAAAAAAAGGAGUUAUUAAAAUACAGACUUUGUUUGGAUAUAAGCCAUAUGAUAAUAAAGCCUUUGAUGAUGGGAAAAAAAGAUAUAGCAAAGAAGAGAUGUUUCUUCCAUAAAAGGGGGAUCAUGGAAGCUGAUAAAGAUGACACACAACAAAUUCUUAAGGAGCAUUCGCCAGAUGAAUUUAUAAAAGAUGAACAAAAUAAGGGACUAAUUGAUGAAAUUACAAAGAAAAAUAUUCAACUAAAGAAGGAGAUCCAAAAGCUUGAAACGGAGUUACAAGAGGCUACCAAAGAAUUCCAGAUUAAAGAGGAUAUUCCUGAAACAAAGAUGAAAUUCUUAUCAGUUGAAACUCCUGAGAAUGACAGCCAGUUGUCAAAUAUCUCCUGUUCGUUUCAAGUGAGCUCGAAAGUUCCUUAUGAGAUACAAAAAGGACAAGCACUUAUCACCUUUGAAAAAGAAGAAGUUGCUCAAAAUGUGGUAAGCAUGAGUAAACAUCAUGUACAGAUAAAAGAUGUAAAUCUGGAGGUUACGGCCAAGCCAGUUCCAUUAAAUUCAGGAGUCAGAUUCCAGGUUUAUGUAGAAGUUUCUAAAAUGAAAAUCAAUGUUACUGAAAUUCCUGACACAUUGCGUGAAGAUCAAAUGAGAGACAAACUAGAGCUGAGCUUUUCAAAGUCCCGAAAUGGAGGCGGAGAGGUGGACCGCGUGGACUAUGACAGACAGUCCGGGAGUGCAGUCAUCACGUUUGUGGAGAUUGGAGUGGCUGACAAGAUUUUGAAAAAGAAAGAAUACCCUCUUUAUAUAAAUCAAACCUGCCAUAGAGUUACUGUUUCUCCAUACACAGAAAUACACUUGAAAAAGUAUCAGAUAUUUUCAGGAACAUCUAAGAGGACAGUGCUUCUGACAGGAAUGGAAGGCAUUCAAAUGGAUGAAGAAAUUGUGGAGGAUUUAAUUAACAUUCACUUUCAACGGGCAAAGAAUGGAGGUGGAGAAGUAGAUGUGGUCAAGUGUUCUCUAGGUCAACCUCACAUAGCAUACUUUGAAGAAUAGACUUAACAGAAUCAUGAAAACUAUAGCUUUUUAACCCGGAUUACUGUAAAUGUUUGACAAAAAUGAAUAUGCUUUUCCUUAAAAAAUGAAAACUUUAAUUUUUACCAUCCAUUUAUGUUUAGAUACAAAACUUAUUUCCAUGUUUCUGAAUCUUCUUUGUUUCAAAUGGUGCUGCAUGUUUUCAACUACAAUAAGUGCACUGUAAUAAAAAGUUUUGUUUAUA